AGUGUGGGACUGGGGCGGAACGCCGCCCGGCCGCGGGUCGGGCUCUGUGUCAGCAGCCGGGCGGGCGCUCGGGCGGGACAUGGCAGCCUGUACAGCCCGGCGGGCCCUGGCCGUGGGCAGCCGCUGGUGGUCCCGGUCGCUGACUGGGGCCCGGUGGCCAAGGCCGCUCUGUGCGGCGGCCGGAGCUGGAGCCUUCUCGCCAGCGUCGACCACGACGACGCGGAGGCACCUCUCGUCCCGAAACCGACCAGAGGGCAAAGUGUUGGAGACAGUUGGUGUGUUUGAGGUGCCAAAACAGAAUGGAAAAUAUGAGACCGGGCAGCUUUUCCUUCAUAGCAUUUUUGGCUACCGAGGUGUCGUCCUGUUUCCCUGGCAGGCCAGACUGUAUGACCGGGAUGUGGCUUCUGCAGCUCCAGAAAAAGCAGAGAACCCUGCUGGCCAUGGCUCCAAGGAGGUGAAAGGCAAAACUCACACUUACUAUCAGGUGCUGAUUGAUGCUCGUGACUGCCCACAUAUAUCUCAGAGAUCUCAGACAGAAGCUGUGACCUUCUUGGCUAACCAUGAUGACAGUCGGGCCCUCUAUGCCAUCCCAGGCUUGGACUAUGUCAGCCAUGAAGACAUCCUCCCCUACACCUCCACUGAUCAGGUUCCCAUCCAACAUGAACUCUUUGAAAGAUUUCUUCUGUAUGACCAGACAAAAGCACCUCCUUUUGUGGCUCGGGAGACGCUAAGGGCCUGGCAAGAGAAGAAUCACCCCUGGCUGGAGCUCUCCGAUGUUCAUCGGGAAACAACUGAGAACAUACGUGUCACUGUCAUCCCCUUCUACAUGGGCAUGAGGGAAGCCCAGAAUUCCCACGUGUACUGGUGGCGCUACUGUAUCCGUUUGGAGAACCUUGACAGUGAUGUGGUACAGCUCCGGGAGCGGCACUGGAGGAUAUUCAGUCUCUCUGGCACCUUGGAGACAGUGCGAGGCCGAGGGGUAGUGGGCAGGGAACCAGUGUUAUCCAAGGAGCAGCCUGCGUUCCAGUAUAGCAGCCACGUCUCGCUGCAGGCUUCCAGUGGGCACAUGUGGGGCACGUUCCGCUUUGAAAGACCUGAUGGCUCCCACUUUGAUGUUCGGAUUCCUCCCUUCUCCCUGGAAAGCAAUAAAGAUGAGAAGACACCACCCUCAGGCCUUCACUGGUAGGCCAGCUGAGGCCCCAAGUGCCCAGGCUUGGUCACCGGGAAGAACAACUCUCAUCCCACAAUUGCUGCAGAACUCUUCUCUCCCCAUCAUGGGCCACAGUGGGUCUCUUAAUUUGAUUGUGGGGUUCUUUUUGUGGGGAGGGGUGGUAUAACUUUUCUUCAGAAGACCCAUGUGGGACACCUCCAAGGCUGGCCUCCUCAUAAGCCCUGCCUACACCAUGUUCCAGUAAACCUCUCCACCAAGGAACUGUGUUCAGCUGCCACAGGCCUGGAGGAGUUUCCUGGCCUGUCACGUGAGGUUUGAUCAGUAAACCAGUGCACGCUUGGCCACCCUUGCCAUUUCUGCUCCCAGAGUCUCAGGCUCCCCUUCUGACCCAGUGUGCGCCCUUGACUGCUUUCUUUGCUGCCCUUCCAGGGAGCUGCCCCCCUGGUAGGGCAUGUGCCUGUUUCCCUCUCAGCCUGGAGGCUGGCUGGACAUCUCCUAGGGUCACUGUGCCUCUCAGCUAGUUGGCGGGGGUGCUGGACUGGACUCUUGUUCACUUUACCUUCUGCCAAAUGCAGAGAGGGAGGCCAGUGUCAGGGUCGGAGUGGCCUGGCUCUUAGCACUGACCGACCAUUGCCAUUUCUGGCCUCGCUAGGCCCAGGAGAGGAGGGAGGCAAGCCAGUCGGGUUUCCUGGAGCAAUGGGUGUGCCAGCCCUCAGCAUGACUCUGCCAAGCAUCCAGACCACAAAUGCAGGAAUUUGGCUGAGGAGCAGCUUUAGGUAUGGAUUGAUGACUAAGUCAAGCUACUUCCUGAGCUUCUCUCAGAUUUCCAAGAGCCAGAGAUGAAUUGUGCUGCAUCUUGCCCCAAUUCUUAGGAUUUCUUUUCCUCCGCCACUGCAGUGAUUGUUAGAGGUAGUUUUCUUGAAUUAAUAUUAAAUCACAGUUCCAGCCCUUGUUAUUCUUGUCCUUAGUCCUCCAGGGGGAGCUGGGGUUGCAGGGCAACAGUACAGUCGCGCUUACGACCUGGCUAGAACACAAGGUCAGAUGAUAAACAGAAGCACAGGAACUCAGCCCAUGGCCGCAAGCUGGUCAAGGCCUGCUCACUGUAAACAUGGCUCUGUACCAUUGAGUUUAACACAAUUUUAUUAGAAAUUAGUGUUUGCUUCCAUCACUUAUGCUGAGCAACCAAAUAUUACAGUUAUGUGAUAAAGGAAAAAUUCUUUCCUGCCCAGGACCUGCGCCAUCCUUUAGGCCGACCUUGGUCACAUACCAAAUUCAAUAAAACCCAAUACUGGCCUGUGUUGUUAACAGCAGGCUGCCAGGUUUCUCAGAAACUGACAAGAAAAUCUGACCUUCAUCCAUACUUUGUUUACUUACCCCUGGGCUGCUUGGAGUUGAAAAAUGCACACAGCCAAGAGUUGCUUUCUGAAUAGGGCUGGAAACUUUCAAAGAAAACCCCCAAACUUUUAAGUCACAAAGUCUGAUUAAAGAAGCUAAGAUCA